GGUGACCAGCAGCAGGAGGAGAAAGAACAUGGCGGGCGCAUCAGAGCUCGGGACCGGCCCAGGAGCAGCGGGUGGAGAUGGAGAUGAUUCGCUAUACCCGAUCGCGGUUUUAAUCGACGAGCUCCGCAAUGAAGACGUGCAGCUCCGACUCAACAGUAUUAAGAAGUUAUCAACAAUUGCCCUAGCACUUGGAGUAGAAAGGACCCGAAGUGAAUUGUUGCCAUUUCUUACAGAUACAAUUUAUGAUGAAGAUGAGGUACUAUUAGCUCUUGCUGAGCAGCUGGGAAAUUUCACUGGCCUAGUGGGAGGUCCUGACUUUGCCCACUGUCUGCUGCCUCCUUUGGAAAAUCUGGCAACUGUGGAAGAGACUGUUGUUCGUGACAAGGCUGUGGAGUCCCUGAGACAGAUCUCCCAGGAGCAUACUCCUGUUGCUCUGGAAGCUUAUUUUGUACCUCUGGUGAAACGCUUAGCAAGUGGGGAUUGGUUCACCUCUCGCACAUCUGCAUGUGGUUUGUUCAGCGUUUGCUAUCCCAGGGCAUCAAAUGCUGUUAAAGCAGAAAUCAGACAGCAAUUCCGUUCCUUGUGCUCAGAUGACACACCAAUGGUACGACGUGCUGCUGCUUCCAAAUUGGGUGAAUUUGCAAAAGUUUUGGAAUUAGACAGUGUGAAAAGUGAAAUUGUUCCACUGUUCACUAGUCUAGCUUCAGAUGAACAGGAUUCAGUGCGCCUCCUUGCUGUGGAAGCUUGUGUCAGUAUUGCCCAGUUAUUGUCUCAGGAUGACCUUGAGACUUUGGUGAUGCCUACACUUCGACAAGCAGCAGAAGAUAAAUCUUGGCGCGUUCGCUAUAUGGUGGCUGACAGAUUUUCAGAGCUCCAGAAAGCCAUGGGUCCUAAAAUCACCCUAAAUGACCUCAUCCCCGCCUUUCAGAACCUACUUAAAGACUGUGAAGCUGAAGUCCGGGCAGCUGCUGCCCACAAAGUAAAAGAACUUGGUGAGAACUUGCCCAUUGAAGAUAGAGAGACCAUAAUUAUGAAUCAAAUUCUGCCUUAUAUAAAGGAAUUAGUAUCCGAUACCAAUCAACAUGUCAAAUCGGCUCUAGCUUCUGUAAUUAUGGGAUUGUCUACUAUUUUGGGCAAAGAAAAUACCAUUGAACAUCUUCUACCUCUUUUCUUAGCUCAGUUAAAGGAUGAGUGUCCUGACGUUCGUUUGAAUAUCAUCUCCAAUUUGGAUUGUGUAAAUGAAGUGAUUGGAAUCCGUCAGCUCUCUCAGUCUCUCCUUCCUGCCAUAGUGGAGCUGGCAGAAGAUGCCAAAUGGAGGGUCCGCCUGGCCAUCAUUGAGUAUAUGCCGCUGCUGGCAGGCCAGCUGGGUGUGGAAUUCUUUGAUGAAAAGCUGAAUUCUUUAUGUAUGGCUUGGCUCGUGGACCAUGUAUACGCCAUCCGAGAAGCUGCCACCAACAACCUCAUGAAACUAGUUCAGAAGUUUGGUACAGAGUGGGCCCAAAAUACUAUUGUUCCCAAAGUGUUAGUAAUGGCAAAUGAUCCUAAUUACUUGCAUAGAAUGACCACUUUAUUCUGCAUUAAUGCACUGUCUGAGGCCUGUGGUCAGGAAAUAACUACUAAGCAAAUGCUGCCCAUCGUAUUAAAAAUGGCAGGAGACCAAGUAGCAAAUGUUCGCUUCAAUGUGGCCAAAUCUCUACAAAAGAUUGGACCAAUUCUAGAUACCAAUGCUUUACAGGGAGAAGUGAAGCCAGUACUACAGAAGUUAGGUCAAGAUGAAGACAUGGAUGUCAAAUACUUUGCACAGGAAGCUAUAAGUGUGGUGGCACAAAGGCUGAGGAAGCUAGAAUUUCCUGUGAAGGACAGUGGAGAACCCAGUGUCCCUCGGGCUGACAAGAACCACUUCCCAAGACCCACAGUGCCUGGAGAGGACAUGGGGAAGGAUAAAGCAGCACAAGAAGCUCUCGGAUGUGUGUUCAGAGAUCCUGAAAUACAUACAAUAAUUGCUGCACUUUAAACCAUAAUCACAGGAUGAGUUUUAGUGCCUGUAAAUUGAGGAUACUCUCCAAAUAGCACUGGAAUCUGGAUAACUUGCUUCACCCAGUCUGCAGCUUUCUGCCUAAAUGCAUAUAGUGAAGUGGGAGCAGAAUUCAGCUACCCAGCCUCGAUGAAGAGUUACACAUCCUUUGUAAUUAUAAUAGGAGUGAAGAAGACAAUUAUGAGGAAAUGAAAGCUGACAAAUGAGAGGUGGAGAGUGAUAGAGAUGAAGCUGACCCAUUGCACAAACUGAAUGUGGAUCGGCCAACACUGACGUCAAUGCAUACUUUGUUGCCCACCAGCACGAAAAGGUCAGUUGCACAGUUCAUUUCCAAACAUCAGUCACUCUCCCAUCUGACAGGAGGGAAGGGAACAAUCAUCACAGUUGAGAUGAAAUGUGAUCCUGCUGACCAAUGUAAGACAUCUAUUUGUCCAGUCAGAGAGUUCAAUGAGCUAAGAAGCAAAUAAAUAAUCUUCCUUAGCUUAAAUGAAGGGGAAGAGAAAUGAAGAGGGAAAAAAAAAUCAAAUCAAACCAAACCCUUUGAGCCAUCUUCCAUAUUCCCAGCUUACUGUGGAAUGCUAAGUAGGACUUAAGGAUACAAAGUUUCAUUGUGCUUUUUGAUGUAAAGCUCUUUUUACUUUUUACGUAAUGCUAGUGGCAGAAGGAUAACAAAUGGAAGACUUACAAUAAAUAUUUUCCCAAUAAAAAUAAAAUACUUAAAAAUUUUUAAAAAAUAUUUUUCCUAUCUUUGCCUCUCCUACCCUUUUUCAGUUCUAGGGGACAAAUCUGAAAUCAUAUAUACAGAAACCUUGACUCAAGGUCAUCUAGUAAGUAGGAAGGUUGCUAGAAGCAAUGAUGGGCCACUGCCUCAAAUCAGAAAGGAAGCAUUCCUCUUGGGCUAAAGACAAGUGACUCGUGAUGUACAGGUCAGAUUAAUCAGGCUAAUUAUACAAUACUAAUUACAUUUAAGGUCUCUCUCAGCAAAAAAUUAAGUUGCAUCAACCAGAGACAAUUGAGAAUAUGUGAAAAACUUUCCUUGGUCCUAAAAGGUUUGUAUUAAUAAGGCUUUAAAGCCUUAGUUAAUUAAAAAAACAUGCCGAGAGGGUUAUAUGGCUAUUAAAAUUUUAAGGCUUUGUUUUCACAGGGAAUCAAUUAUACAUUGAAUACAAAUAAUAGCUACCUUGUAUUGAGUGUUUACAUGGUGCCAGGAGCUUUAUCUAACAAUUUAUUUAACAAACAGUUAACUAGCACUGUGUGCCGGGCACUGUUCUAAGUACCCUACAAAUAUCAACUCAAGUAAUAAUCACUAUGAGAUAUGAACUUUUAUCACUCUCCCUUUACAGAUAAGGAAACUGAGAAGAGAGAAGUCAGGAAACGUGGUCAAGGUCACAAAGCUAGUAAGUGGCAGAGAUAGGAUUCAAACUCAGGUAUCCUGACUACACAGCCCAUACUCUGACCUAUUACCCUACAUCGACUCCCUGUCUCCAAUAUUAUCACCAAUCCCUAUAAUCUGUUCCUGAAAAACAGAUUUGUAUUUAAUAGAUAUGGAAACUCAGGCCUAGAAAGUGUAAAUAAUCGGCCCAAGGUUAUAGCUACUAAGUGGCACAGACAGAAUUUGCACCAGCACUGCUACUCAACUCAGUACUCUACAUGAAGCCCUGUUUGACGUGUGAUUAAUUCAUAGAUUUUUAUCCUUAUUUAAGUAUUUAUUAUAAACAUUUUAGAUUGGGAAAGUUGGAGAAUAAAACUAAAUAUUCCUCAUCUAUUUUAUUCUCAACUUAAUGCCUGAACAGCCAGGGCCAAAACAGGUGGAAAUAGUACUGCAAUUACUAAAACUACUGAAAGCCAGUAUUUGCAUUCAGCCUCCUACUGUGAAUGUCCUCACACUCACUUUUUACAAAGGUUGCAGGUCUCAUGGUUGAGGCAAUGAGUACACACUGGUGUGGGUGAAUCCAUGGCUCAUUAGUGUCUCAAGUUUUUUUUUUUUUUUUGAGACGGAGUCUCCUCUGUCACCAGGCUGGAGGGCAGUGGCACAAUCUCGGCUCACUGCAACCUCUGACUCCCUGGUUCAAGCGAUUCUCUCCUGCCUCAGCCUCCUGAGUAGCUGGGAUUACAGGCAUGCACCACCAUGCCCAGCUAAUUUUUGUAUUUUUAGUAGAGACGGGGUUUCACCAUGUUGGCCAGGAUGGUCUCGAAAUCCUGCCCUCGUGAUCCGCCCACCUUGGCCCCUCAAAGUGCUGGGAUUACAGGCGUGAGCCACUGCGCCCGGCCUGUCUCAAGUUUUUACCCACGGGGAAAACAAAACCUGGAAACUGAUCUCAAAGCCAUGUUUCUGUUAUUUAUUAAAAUGAACCAUGUUUGAUACUUCUAUUCCAUUUUGUUUUAUAAACACAAAAAUAUUUUAAUUUUGUGCUUCUCUUCAAUUUCAAUAUACAAGAUGGCUAAAGCAGUUCAUUUAUUCAGCUUAUUUUGCAAUUAAAGAGAUUUUCAUAAGCCAAAAAAAAAACCCAGAAAAAAGUAUAAUUUGAGGGAAUAACUUUGUAAGGGUUCUUGUAAUUUCUUCCCACAGAGCCCUAUUUUUCCCAUGUGUUAGAUUCCAUUAAGAUUUAAGAGUUCUCAGAGAUAAGAAGAUGAUCCUUAAAGAAAAUCAGGGCCAUCAAGAAGUUAUAAAAUUUACAGAUAAAAAUAAAUAUCCUAGAGAAAUUCUUUAAAGACAUUGGAAUCCAUCUAAACACUUUAUAGCACGUGAAUGAUCUGGCCCAUGCCCGCCUCUCCUGGCUUUUUUCCUAUCAUUCUCACUGGCUAAUACCUGCAGUUUCCUUACCACUCCAAUUCGCUCUGGCCUCUCAGCCUUUGCAUGUGUGGAUCCAUCUGCUUGAGGCAGAUACCCCAGCCUCGAUCUCUAUCUCUCUCUCUCCCUCUCUCCUUUUUGUGUUUUUUUUUUUUUUUUUUUUUUUUUUUUUUUUUUUUUUGAGACUGAGUCUCGCUCUGUUGCCUAGGCUGGAGUGCAGUGGCAGGAUCUCAGCUCACUGCAACCUCCACCUCCUGGGUUCAAGCAAUUCUCCUGCCUCAGCCUCCGGAGUAGCUGGGACUACAGGCGCAUGCUGCCAUUCCUGGCUAAUUUUCUGUAUUUUAGUAGAGACGAGGUUUCACCAUGUUGCCCAGGCUGGUCUCGAACUCCUGAGCUCAGGCAAUCUGCCCGUCUUGGCCUCCCAAAGUGCUAGGAUUACAGGCAUAAGCCACCGAGCCUGGCCUCUCCCUCUUUCUUUCUCUGUCUCCCCGAUCCCCAAUCCUGCCACAAAUACCUUCUUGUUAAUCAAGUGUUAGCUAAUAAUUUCCCUGAUUCUUCCAGACAGAGUUAGUCUUUCUCCUAGCCUCAUGUCCCUGAAAACAAUGAUCUUUUUGUGUUAUAUUAACUUAAAGGUCUGGUUCUUAUUUGAUUAACUCCUUGAGGUAAGAGCAGAGUUAAGCUUUUUGUCACUGCUGCUGUUUUUGUCUUGAAAUGUAUGAAUAUCCAGGACUUAGUCCAAGAGCAGAGUAGAAGCUUAAUAAACAUUUACUAAAAUUUUUGAGGAUAGUGGAGAUGAUAGAGAAUUAAGUGUGGGCAAGAAAAUUUGAGUGCUUAGAUAUACUCUGUGCACACAUGUGUGUGUGUGUCUGCUUGUAAUGAAUGGAAGCAGGGACACUAAAUGUACAACCAUAGAAUGAUGGACCCCAAAAUUCAAUUAGUGAGUACCCCUUUAGGAAGAAGUGACACAGAAUGCUUGGAAAUGACAAAAUGGUGUAGUGGGAGAAGGACAGAUACUGUGGUCAGAGAGACCUAGGUUUGAAUUCCAGGUCUGCUACUUAUUAUCUGUGUCAGCUCGGCCAAUUUUUUAAUCUCUUUGCAUCUCAGCUUUCUCAUCUAGUAACUGGCAAUAGCUAAGCGGCUCCCAAGAUUGCUGUGAAGAUGAAGUAAGUAUCUAGCAGAAUACCUGAAAACAGUGAGGGCCCAAUUAAAUGUGAGUCAUCACACUGUCUUCACCAGAGAGAACUUCACCAAUCUGAAUUUUUAUCUGACUUCUAUAUAAUUAGAAGGGCUUGAAGAUUAGAUACUAAAAAGCAAAAAUAAAAACCAAAAAGACAAAACAAAAACCUAAGAUAUCACACAAUGACAUCAGAAACACUGAUUUGACCCACGUAUAUUUUAUGCCAGAAUUAUAAUAGACAUACUAUAGCCAGGCAAAACUUGGUUAUAACGUCAAAGCAAUAUUCUGUUUUUUGUUUGCAAGUUUCUUUGGUGUCUUACUUUGACAUUUUCUUUUGAGAUGUUAGUGACAGCACUUUGUAAUUCCUACAGCAUAUGAUUUACACACCUAUAACCUUUCUCUGCCUAAAAAAACUCCUAGAACACAUGUGCAUGUAUGUUUCUUGUAGCACUAUUUACAAUAGCAAAGACUUGGAACCAACCCAAAUGCCUGUCAAUGAUAGACUGGAUACAGCAAACGUGGCACAUAUACACAAUGGAAUACUACGCAGACAUAAAAAAAGAAUGAGUUCAUGUCCUUUGCAGGGACAUGGAUGAAGCUGGAAACCAUCAUCCUCAGCAAACUAAAGGAAUAGAAAACCAAACACCACAUGUUCUCACUCAUAAGUGGGAGUUGAACAAUGAGAAUACAUGGACACAGGGAGGGGAACAUCACACAUGGGGGCCUCUUUGGGGGUGAGGGGAGGCGGGGAGGGAGAGCCUUAGGACAAAUACCUAAUCCAUGCAGGGCUUAAAACCUAGAUGACGAGUUGAUAGGUGCAACAAACCACCAUGGCACAUGUAUACCUACGUAACAAAGCUGCACAUUCAGCACAUGUAUCCCAGAACUUAAAGUAAAAAAAUAAUAAUAAAAAAUAAAAAAUAAAUAAAAUAGUUCUCUUGGAAAAAAAAACAACUCCUAGAACUCCUUUGUGCUAUUGUUUUGGUAAAUAUUUCGUUUUGGUAAUAAGGGAAUGUAAAGGUGUAGCAGGAGUUUUCCCCCUUCUUUCUACAGAGCUAAGGACUUAAAAAAAAAAAAAAAAAGAAAGACCUUCUCUGAAAAAGACAAUUUUAGGGCAGCCGAUGCUUUCAAGGAGCAUUAAACAAAAUAUCCCAGUGAAGUUCCUCACAGAAGGUUGGCAAAAAAGAGUGAAAUAAAUGACACCAAAUGGAAGGGCCAAAAGCAGAGGAAGGGAAAAAAACAAAUGGAAGUGAACAGACAUAAACUAUGAAAGUAUUCUAAUUUUGUGCAUCACAUUUUCACAACAAAAAUGACAAAUUGAUAUAAAUCUUUAUAUAUACGUGUAUAUGUGUGAUAUAUAUAUAUAUAUACACAUACACACACACACAAAUGAAUAUAACAAAUUAACUUAAAAACAUUUUGUCUUAUUCAGGCAAUCCCAUUAGAAAAAAAAAAUCACAGACUAUAGAAUGGAAAAUCCAUUACAUAUCCUGUAACAUAUGUAAUAUUGACAUUUAAAAUGAGUAAAAAUAAUUUGCCUUCCCCUAAUUGCCUAAGACAAAAACUAAUGGGAAAUGGCACAGAAACAAAUCAGUUCAAUGUACAAACAUGAGGGUUUUACCUUAUAUUUUACACCAUAUACAGCAAACCGAGGAAGCUACUUUGUCCCUAAACUUACUAAGUUCAAUGAGUAUCCAACCUAACAGGUCAAUUAAUAAUUUCUUGGUCAGUCCCUGUCAUCUGGAUGUCUCCCUGCUCUUCUUUAACAAUCUUAGAACAAAACACCACCAUGUGUAACUUUGCUAAGCUUUUAACCCACACUCUUUCUCUUCAAAACCCAAGUCAAACAAAAUCUCCCUUACAUACCUUCAACCUCUACUGCUGCUGCUCUAGUUCAGACUCAUGUUUUCUUAAAUGGACUAUUGCACUAGAUUCCUUAUUAGUCUUCCUGUCUUCCACCUCACCCACAUCUCCCACCUAUCUUAACUCUGCUGCCAGAGACAUAUUUCUGACAUGCAAAUCUAAUCAUGUUAUCCCAAUUCCACUUUACCCCUACCCAUGCCCUAUAAUUUUCAGUAGGCUAGACUCCCCAUUACCUACAGAAUAAACUAUAAAAUCUUUGACAUGGCAUUCAAGAUGUUUCAUAUUCUGGUCUUUACUUAUCUGCUCCCCCUGUAUCAAUCCUGCAUGCCUACAGAUUUUACAUGUAACCAGUUUUGAAUUUACAGUUCCCCAACAUUCCAAUCUCUGUCUACCUGCCUGCAACAUUCUGCUUCUGUUUAUCUUCCUGACAAGCUUCUCUAACUUCUCUCUCAAGUCUAAGUUCAAAUAAUUCCUUCUUUGUGAAGCUUCCCUGACUCUUCAGGUAGACUGCUUGUUCCCUCACCUAUACUCCCAUGCAGUUUGUAUAUACUUUUAAAAUUGCAACUAUCAUACUGUAUUUUUUCAGUUUUAUUAAAAUGUAAUUGACAAAAAUUGUGUAUAUUCAAGGUGUACAUGCUAUUUUUAUAUAUGGAUAUGUUGUGAAAUGAUUUCCACAUAUCAUAUUGUACUUAACAUAGCACAGUACCUGAUACAUAUUUAUUGAGUGAAUGAGAGUUUUGACUAUGUAAAUAAAGAGACUGAGAAUAUAAAAUAAAACAUUUUACAACUGUGAAAAGGCAAGGAGAAAAACAGGCAAACUAAUCUCUACCCAACUUAAUUUUCAUGUUAUAAAUCAAAACCCUAUCGUAUCAGAUCAAGGAAAGGUGCUUUUCUGUCUCAACUAUUUCUCAUUCUACCUCCAUCACUUCUUUUGCCUUUUCUCUGCUUCUGGCUGUAGCCAUCAGUCAUAAUUAGGAGAGCAGGCCAGAGUACCAGCAACCAGCAUUACUCCUCCAGCCCUGUCUUUUCUCCAGUCACUCUGACACUCAGAUAAAUGUACCUCUUCCAGCAGAGCACCCCGAAACCCUGCCAAUGGAAUCUGGACACAUCAGACCCCAGAUGUAGCUCUGACCUGUGUAUAUUAAUAAUGAACUCAUUCCCUUACUUUUAAUUACACACAGAACUAAGGAAAUGAAUAAAAUGGACUUUGAGAUAGCCUGAUGUCAUCAGGUAGAAAUGCUGCUGAAUCUGCGCCUGCAGGUCUGUUUCCACACACUGAGUGCAGUGGCUCACUUCGGAUCUUAUUAGAGCCAGUUGUGUCCCAGUUACCUGCUAUUUUGAUAUUCAUGUUGUUAUCCAGCAGGAGAUUUUCAGCUUUGAGGUCACGGUGCACAAUCUUCCGACCAUGACAAUAAUCAACAGCAGACAGGAUUUGCCAGAAUUUUCGCCUGGCUUCAGACUCAUUUAACCGGCCAUGAUUAGCAAGAUAGUC